GAGCGCGGCCGUGCCCUCUCGAGCGGCUGCGGGGUCCCCGCGGCGCCGGGCUGCUGAGCUGAGGGCCCGCGGCGGCCGCGGCCGGUGCAUGUGCGGCUGCUGGAUGCGGAGGCGGCGGCGACGGCGCGGAUCGGCAGGAUGUUAGGGCAGCAGCAGCAGCAACUGUACUCGUCGGCCGCGCUCCUGACCGGGGAGCGGAGCCGGCUGCUCACCUGCUACGUGCAGGACUACCUUGAGUGCGUGGAGUCGCUGCCCCACGACAUGCAGAGGAACGUGUCUGUGCUGCGAGAGCUGGACAACAAAUAUCAAGAAACGUUAAAGGAAAUUGAUGAUGUCUACGAAAAAUAUAAGAAAGAAGAUGAUUUAAACCAGAAGAAACGUCUACAGCAGCUUCUCCAGAGAGCACUAAUUAAUAGUCAAGAAUUGGGAGAUGAAAAAAUACAGAUUGUUACACAAAUGCUCGAAUUGGUGGAAAAUCGGGCAAGACAAAUGGAGUUACACUCACAGUGUUUCCAAGAUCCUGCUGAAAGUGAACGAGCCUCAGAUAAAGCAAAGAUGGAUUCCAGCCAACCAGAAAGAUCUUCAAGAAGACCCCGCAGGCAGCGGACCAGUGAAAGCCGUGAUUUAUGUCACAUGGCAAAUGGGAUUGAAGACUGUGAUGAUCAGCCACCUAAAGAAAAGAAAUCCAAGUCAGCAAAGAAAAAGAAACGCUCCAAGGCCAAGCAGGAAAGGGAAGCUUCACCUGUUGAGUUUGCAAUAGAUCCUAAUGAACCUACAUACUGCUUAUGCAACCAAGUGUCUUAUGGGGAGAUGAUAGGAUGUGACAAUGAACAGUGUCCAAUUGAAUGGUUUCACUUUUCAUGUGUUUCACUUACCUAUAAACCAAAGGGGAAAUGGUAUUGCCCAAAGUGCAGGGGAGAUAAUGAGAAAACAAUGGACAAAAGUACUGAAAAGACAAAAAAGGAUAGAAGAUCGAGGUAGUAAAGGCCAUCCACAUUUUAAAGGGUUAUUUGUCUUUUAUAUAAUUCGUUUGCUUUCAGAAAAUGUUUUAGGGUAAAUGCAUAAGACUAUGCAAUAAUUUUUAAUCAUUAGUAUUAAUGGUGUAUUAAAAGUUGUUGUACUUUGUCUGUGACCUUAAUUUUCUGCACUGAGUUACCAAAUAUUUCCAACCAGGUAGUCUUCAGAUCACCUGAUGAAAGGAGCAGGGAACAGGAAGAGGGUGGUGUAAACAUUAUAAAAAUUUCACAAACCAUGCCUAUUUCAUUUUCACUUAAAACUGCAAUGUUAUUUUUUGGGUAAACACAAAAGUUUCACUAGCAUUUUAGUUAUACAUGCUUAAAAAAAUGUUAGAUGUAGUGGGAUUUCUCUUAAGCAUCAAAUGAUCUUGGGUACUUUAAAAUACAGACACUAUGCCAUUUGAGCUGCUUUUUCCCUAGUCCUAUUUAUACGUUGGCUUGUUCAUCUCUAGUCUUCUAGGAGUUUAAGGAACUGGAGAUAAGAGUAAUUUGGGAUUCCAUGUGGAAUAAUGUGCUCUUAUGAGAGUACGUGCUGCUGUCUUUUGCUUAGUAGCAUUUUGAUCCACUGUCAGUAGCCCAUUUGUCAAUGCCUUGCUGCUGCUUUGUAGAUAUACUUAGUCUAGUGCUUAAUAAGGGAGUUGUUUUGUGUUUUCUUUUAAUUGGGACAGGUAAGAGUAGUUAGCAUACCAAAAAUAUACAUUGGCUUACAUUGGCAAACUUUGGGUUAUAUAGUAUCACGGCUCAAGGUUGAACAAUUUAAAAAUACAUCUUAAUUAAUAGUAUUUUCCAUGUGACCUGCUGCCAGGAUGCGUAGCCACAGGCCUAUCAGUGGAAAGGGGCAUAUAGUAGUCUUUAAAUAUUGCCUUUAUGUCAGAGAGUUGUUUUAAAUGGUUUUGCUAGUGGUUAUUGUUCAUUUCUGUCCCAAUCAGUGACUAUUUUAAAUAAUAGUGUAUUUACUGUCUUAACUUCUAGUAUUGGUGCUGUUUGAUGUUUUCACAUUUAAUUAACUUAUUUCAUCAUCAUAAUGCAAUUAAUGUAUUUGUAAAUUGAAUUUUCCAAGAUUCUGAUAUUUGAAGGGUAAGCAUCUUGAUGGAUAUAUGUCCAUAUGUUUAGAGAAGGUUUUGGUUUUGGGGGCAGCAGAUUGACUAGUUCUUUAAAUCUGUGUGUAACGUAUGUUUUAUUCCUCAUUUCUUCCUAAUCUGAUGAUCUUGAUUCUUUUUGAUUAACAUGAAAAAUCCUGUCUGCUUGUUUUGGGAAAAAAAAAUGCUUUUUUUCUCUUCUAGCUCUCCUGUGUGACUUUUAGGCAUGUCAUUUCACCUUGUCUGGGUGUCAGGUCAUUCACCUGUAAAAUGAGUUGGCUUAAAUAUCUCCGAGAUUCCUUGGAAAUUUCUACUAUUUGCACUAUAGUGAGGAUUUUAAUAAUGACAUGACUUCUCUUUUCA